ACUCUGUCGCCGCCGUCAGACCGGAAUUGCCGGUGCCGCCGCCACCGCUGUCUGUGCGCCCACCUCUGCUGCUACCAUGGGGAUCUUAGAGAAGAUCUCGGAGAUCGAGAAGGAGAUCGCUCGGACACAGAAGAACAAGGCCACUGAGUAUCAUCUGGGCCUGCUGAAAGCUAAGCUCGCCAAGUAUCGGGCCCAGCUCCUGGAACCGUCCAAAUCGGCCUCGUCCAAAGGAGAGGGCUUUGAUGUCAUGAAGUCGGGUGAUGCCCGUGUGGCGCUGAUUGGAUUUCCCUCUGUGGGUAAGUCCACAUUCUUGAGUCUGAUGACCUCCACGGCCAGCGAGGCAGCGUCCUAUGAGUUCACCACUCUGACGUGUAUUCCUGGGGUCAUUGAAUACAAAGGUGCCAACAUCCAGCUCCUGGACCUUCCUGGAAUCAUUGAAGGCGCAGCCCAAGGAAAAGGCCGUGGCCGGCAGGUGAUCGCUGUGGCGCGCACGGCUGACGUCAUCAUCAUGAUGCUGGAUGCCACCAAGGGAGAGGUGCAGAGGUCUCUGCUGGAGAAGGAGCUGGAGUCUGUGGGCAUCCGCCUCAACAAGCACAAGCCUAACAUCUACUUCAAGCCCAAGAAAGGUGGUGGCAUCUCCUUUAACUCGACAGUCACGCUGACCCAGUGCUCGGAAAAGCUGGUGCAGCUCAUCCUGCACGAAUACAAGAUCUUCAAUGCAGAAGUGCUUUUCCGAGAAGACUGCUCCCCGGACGAGUUCAUCGAUGUGAUCGUGGGCAACCGGGUGUACAUGCCCUGCCUGUAUGUUUAUAACAAAAUCGACCAGAUCUCCAUGGAAGAGGUGGACCGCCUGGCCCGAAAACCCAACAGUGUGGUCAUCAGCUGCGGCAUGAAGCUGAACCUGGACUAUCUGCUGGAGAUGCUUUGGGAGUACUUGGCCCUGACCUGCAUCUACACCAAGAAGAGAGGACAAUCACAAGAUGGCAGUGUGGGCCCUGAUGUGUGGCUGACGUUCUCCCCAUCCUGCCCUGCAGAGAGGCCAGACUUCACAGACGCCAUCAUUCUCCGGAAAGGGGCCUCAGUGGAGCACGUGUGCCACCGCAUCCACCGGUCACUCGCCAGCCAGUUCAAGUACGCCCUGGUGUGGGGCACCAGCACCAAGUACAGUCCGCAGCGGGUGGGCCUGACCCACACCAUGGAGCAUGAGGACGUCAUCCAGAUCGUGAAGAAGUAACGGCGCCUGCCGGGCCUCCCGCCCACCUGCCUCGUCUCCCUGGGGAGGUGGUCCCACUGGGACACACAAACACCCAAACAGAAAAAUACAAAUACACGUACCCCAGGAAGGGGUCCCUCAAGUCUCUGCUAUUUACAGAAGUUUCUUCAGUAGGCAGACGAAGAGUGUGUUGGGGCAAAGGGGCUCGGUUGGAGGCAUUUCCCAUAAGACUGAGCCCUCUCAUGGGGGUUUUGAGUUUGUAGUGCUGAGCCUGCAUCUGUGCCUCCCAGCCCCCUGCACUGAGGGAGCAAGUUGCCCACAUGCCCGCCAGCCAGGGCCUAAAGCAGAUGGCAUGCUCAGUGCCAGGCUGGUAGCUGGGCCUGUUUGGGUCCCUGGAGGCUGUGGCUGCUGUCAUGGCACCUCACUCCCUCAGCUCUUGCCAGCUUCUCUGACACUUGGGUUGGGGGCCCUUCCAGGAGGAAACCCCCUUGGGUGCCCCACACAGGGCUCUCCAUGAUGGGAACCAGUGGUUAGUGGCUUCAAAGGCCCAGCUGACACCCUCCACAGCCUAAGGGGUGUCCUAAAGUGCCUCCCCCUGUAUUCCCCCUCCCAGGGCAGCCCCUGCCCAGCACAAAACCCCAGGACCCUGGCUCUGCACGCCUGGGGCAGGGACUUUUGAGUUUAGGAUCUGUAUUUUCUAAGUCCCCAGUUCUCCUGGCUCUCCUUUCUGAAAUAAAGGAUUGAAAACGG